AGUGUUUACUUCCGCUUGACCUGGCCCGGACGCCAGAAAAUGUUCCACGUGGGAUACCCUGCGUGGGGUUCACUGUAGUAGCUGCACUAGGUGAUUCUUGGAGCGGGCCUGAGAGACAAGGACAUGUGGAUCCCAGUGGUCGGGCUUCCUCGGCGGCUGAGGCUCUCCGCCUUGGCGGGCGCUGGUCGCUUUUGCAUUUUAGGGUCUGAAGCGGCGACGCGAAAGCAUUUGCCGGCGAGGAACCACUGUGGGCUCUCUGACUCCUCUCCGCAGCUGUGGCCCGAACCGGAUUUCAGGAAUCCGCCAAGGAAGGCGUCUAAGGCCAGCUUAGACUUUAAGCGUUACGUAACCGAUCGGAGAUUGGCUGAGACCCUGGCGCAAAUCUAUUUGGGAAAACCAAGUAGACCUCCACACCUACUGCUGGAGUGCAAUCCAGGUCCUGGAAUCCUGACUCAGGCAUUACUUGAAGCUGGUGCCAAAGUGGUUGCGCUCGAAAGUGACAAAACUUUUAUUCCACAUUUGGAGUCCUUAGGAAAAAAUCUGGAUGGAAAACUACGAGUGAUUCACUGUGACUUCUUUAAACUAGAUCCUAGAAGUGGUGGAGUAAUAAAACCACCUGCUAUGUCUUCUCGAGGGCUCUUUAAGAAUUUGGGAAUAGAAGCAGUUCCUUGGACAGCAGACAUCCCUUUAAAAGUAGUUGGAAUGUUCCCAAGUAGAGGUGAGAAAAGGGCACUUUGGAAACUCGCAUAUGACUUGUAUUCCUGUACUUCUAUAUAUAAAUUUGGACGAAUAGAAGUAAAUAUGUUUAUUGGUGAAAAAGAAUUCCAGAAACUAAUGGCAGAUCCCGGAAAUCCAGACUUGUAUCAUGUAUUAAGUGUUAUCUGGCAAUUAGCUUGUGAGAUUAAGGUUCUGCACAUGGAGCCUUGGUCAUCAUUUGAUAUAUACACCCGGAAAGGGCCGCUGGAAAACCCAAAGCGUAGGGAAUUAUUAGACCAAUUACAACAAAAGCUGUAUCUUAUUCAAAUGAUUCCUCGUCAAAAUUUAUUUACCAAGAACUUAACACCUAUGAACUAUAAUAUAUUUUUUCACUUGUUAAAGCACUGUUUUGGGAGGCGCAGCGCCACUGUAAUAGACCACUUACGUUCAUUGACUCCACUUGAUGCGAGAGAUAUAUUGAUGCAAAUAGGAAAACAGGAGGAUGAGAAAGUAGUUAACAUGCACCCUCAAGACUUCAAAACACUUUUUGAAACUAUAGAGCGUUCCAAAGAUUGUGCUUAUAAAUGGCUGUAUGAUGAAACCCUGGAAGAUAGGUAGCAACUAGACUGUCGUUUUUGGUGGAGCGGUUCAUUUAUUUGGAAACUAUGACAUGAAAACCAAAUUUGAAAACUCACAUCCUUUCAGCAGAAGGUAACUGUUCUUGUCUUGCACAAGCCAGGCAGAUCAUUUCUCCUAAGCUGAUAUCAUUGGCUUAUUGGAUGAAACAGUGUCUGCUAUUUUAUUCACAAUUGAAUAAAAUGAAAACUUCAAUUAAUUGUGGAUUUGAUCAGAUUGAAUUCGUUUUGUUUCAGAUUCCUAUUUAAAUAUUUCACUUGUACUGUUGCUGAUUUUUGCAUCUUCUUGAAGAGCAAGAGUCUGUACAUUAUUAAGCUUAGAAAGUAAGCAAAACUGAUUUACUGGUUUGCCUUUCAGUUUGUUGAAAUGUAUUGUCAAGUACUGUACAAUGAAAUUGUUUAAAUUUUAAUAUGAUUUAAGCUUUUUAGAAAUUAAAAUAUUUUAAAUAAGAA